AUGCUCUUACUGGAGGCAAAACCAGAGCUGCCAGUGUACAUCCAGCCAGCUCGGCCCCAGAGUUUCCCUUACCAGAAAGCCAAUCAUCACCCGUGUCUCCGCCUCAGUAACAGCCUGGCCGGAACCAAUGGGAGCGAGCCCCAGCUCUUCCUUCUCGCCUCUCUGAGCCCAGGAGCUGCGUCCCCGCGCCUCCUCCUUGCCUACCCGGCGUCCCCGCAGGUAGGGAGCCGACUCGGCUCCCGGGAUCGGUCCAUUGAGAGUCUAGAGUACAAAGAGCAGCGAGAGGCGAGUGUCGAGUACAAAGCCGCGGGGGCGGGGCCAGCGCUCCAGCUGGAGCGAGCGCCGGGCAGGAAGCCGGGGGAGACCCUGACCUCCCAACCCACAUUUCUGACGGGAGUCGGCCCGACACGCCCCUCGGAGAUACUGUGCCUUCUCUCUCCUGGGCGAGAUCUCGGUGGGGGCCGGCAGGCGGGGACGGGGGCACCGGGUCCCGCGGGGCUCCGUCUUCCAUCUGCAGGAUCCCCCGUGCCCCAGCCGGCCGCCAGCCGGAAUCUGUCUGGGUCCCCAACUCUCCCGCCCCUCCCCGCGCUGUUCCAGGGCGGAGUCUGUGGAGUUGAAACCAGGACACGGCGAGAGGAAGAGUUAUAUAACCGGGAGAAGCGAAGAAGGACGAGUGGAGACAGGGACAGACAGCCCGAAAGGAGCCGAGGGAGGUGCAAAGAACGCCGGGGCGAACGAGGAGGAAACGUUAGGAAUGGGAAGGGUUUUGGUGCACAUCAAAGAGCAGGAAUUCACGCGAAGAAGGGGCGUGAUGGCCCAGAAGAAUCACCUGGGCCGUCCGGGGCUUCCCCGCAGUGCCCUCCUCCGCCACCAACAGCAGCUGGGCCCGGGCGGGAGAAGCCUUGGGAAGGGGCGCUGGUACCCGCUCGCUUUCUCUUGGGAAAGCAACUUAAGCCAGAGCCCGGGAAGGCAGCGGCCGAGCAGAUGGGGCCGGAAACCACAGCUCCGCCCAGCCCACCUGGGAGUGUGGGGCGCCAGCUGGGGGGAGGUGGGGAACAGGUAGUCGGCCCUCCCGAGCCAGGCUGGGCAUUAUGGUCGCGACCGGCGAAACGGUGCAGACCGACCGAGACGUGUGGGUCCCCAGGGGCUGAAGAGCGCAGCCUCAGGCGGCUUUACACAGACUCCACGAGGGGAGGGGGGCGCCCGGCUCGCCGCGCAGGCGCAAGGGGGUGCUCGGGCGCGUGCGGCGCAGGGCGGGGGGUGGGCGCGAGCGUGUGGGAGUGCACGUGCGGGUCCCAGGCAGCUGCUGCCUCCCAGCCUCCGCCGCUGCCCCUCCCCUCUCCCUUUCCUGUCGCUAUCAUCCCCCUUCCCCAUUGGCUGCCAGGGCCCUGACGUCAGGGCCGACCGCUGGAGCGGAUUGGGCGGACGGGAGAGUUCGGGAAUCCGGCUCCCAAGUCUCGCCCUCCAGUUACUCUGGCAACAGGACAAGCAACCCAGGGGAGGGAAGGGGAGCCGAGGUCAACGCUGCGCCUCGGUCCCUAACCCCCUCCGGACAACCACCGAGUCCCCUUCGGUCGCGGCGCAGCUCGCUACCUCCCCGC